GCUCUUACAACAUUGGCUGCCGGCGUGACUUUGACCGCUUCCCGGUGCGUUACCGGCAGCUGAACCCACCCGGCGCCACGGGACUUUGACGCGUGCUCUGCGCUUGCCAUGAGACUCCUGGGAGCUGCAGCCGUCGCGGCUCUGGGGCGCGGAAGGGCCCCCGCCUCCCUAGGCUGGCAGAGGAAGCAGGUUAAUUGGAAGGCCUGCCGAUGGUCUUCAUCAGGGGUGAUUCCUAAUGAAAAAAUACGAAAUAUUGGAAUCUCAGCUCACAUUGAUUCUGGGAAAACUACAUUAACAGAACGAGUCCUUUACUACACUGGCAGAAUUGCAAAGAUGCAUGAGGUGAAAGGUAAAGAUGGAGUUGGUGCUGUCAUGGAUUCCAUGGAACUAGAGAGACAAAGAGGAAUCACUAUUCAGUCAGCAGCCACUUACACCAUGUGGAAAGAUGUCAAUAUUAACAUUAUAGAUACUCCUGGGCAUGUGGACUUCACAAUAGAAGUGGAAAGGGCCCUGAGAGUGUUGGAUGGUGCAGUCCUUGUUCUCUGUGCUGUUGGAGGGGUACAGUGCCAGACCAUGACUGUCAAUCGUCAGAUGAAGCGCUACAACGUUCCGUUUCUAACUUUUAUUAACAAAUUGGACCGAAUGGGCUCCAACCCAGCCAGGGCCCUGCAGCAAAUGAGGUCUAAACUAAAUCAUAAUGCAGCGUUUAUGCAGAUACCCAUGGGUUUGGAGGGUAAUUUUAAAGGUAUUGUAGAUCUUAUUGAGGAACGAGCCAUCUAUUUUGAUGGAGACUUUGGGCACUUCCUGAGGGAUUUCCUUCCUCUGCUAUGGAAUUGGGAUCGCAGGUCUGGCAGUCAGAUUGUUCGAUAUGGUGAGAUUCCAGCUGAAUUAAGGGCGGCGGCCACUGACCACCGGCAGGAGCUAAUUGAAUGUGUUGCCAAUUCAGAUGAACAGCUUGGUGAGAUGUUUCUGGAAGAAAAAAUCCCCUCGAUUUCUGAUUUAAAGCUAGCAAUUCGAAGAGCUACUCUGAAAAGAUCAUUUACUCCUGUAUUUUUGGGAAGCGCCUUGAAGAACAAAGGAGUUCAGCCUCUUUUAGAUGCUGUUUUAGAAUACCUCCCAAAUCCAUCUGAAGUCCAGAACUAUGCUAUUCUCAAUAAAGAGGAUGACUCAAAAGAGAAAACCAAAAUCCUAAUGAACUCCAGUAGAGACAAUUCCCACCCAUUUGUAGGCCUGGCUUUUAAACUGGAGGUAGGUCGAUUUGGACAAUUAACUUAUGUUCGCAGUUAUCAGGGAGAGCUAAAGAAGGGUGACACCAUCUAUAACACAAGGACAAGAAAGAAAGUACGGUUGCAACGGCUGGCUCGCAUGCAUGCCGACAUGAUGGAGGAUGUUGAGGAAGUAUAUGCCGGAGACAUCUGUGCAUUGUUUGGCAUUGACUGUGCUAGUGGAGACACAUUCACAGACAAAGCCAACAGCGGCCUUUCUAUGGAGUCAAUUCAUGUUCCUGAUCCUGUCAUUUCAAUAGCAAUGAAGCCUUCUAACAAGAACGAUCUGGAAAAAUUUUCAAAAGGUAUUGGCAGGUUUACAAGAGAAGAUCCCACAUUUAAAGUAUACUUUGACACUGAGAACAAAGAGACAGUUAUAUCUGGAAUGGGAGAAUUACACCUGGAAAUCUAUGCUCAGAGGCUGGAAAGAGAGUAUGGCUGUCCUUGUAUCACAGGAAAGCCAAAAGUUGCCUUUCGAGAGACCAUUACUGCCCCUGUCCCGUUUGACUUUACACAUAAAAAACAAUCAGGUGGUGCAGGCCAGUAUGGAAAAGUAAUAGGUGUCCUGGAGCCUCUGGACCCAGAGGACUACACUAAAUUGGAAUUUUCAGAUGAAACAUUCGGAUCAAAUAUUCCAAAGCAGUUUGUGCCUGCUGUAGAAAAGGGGUUUUUAGAUGCCUGCGAGAAGGGCCCUCUUUCUGGUCACAAGCUCUCUGGGCUCCGGUUUGUCCUGCAAGAUGGAGCACACCACAUGGUUGAUUCUAAUGAAAUCUCUUUCAUCCGAGCAGGAGAAGGUGCUCUUAAACAAGCCUUGGCAAAUGCAACAUUAUGUAUUCUUGAACCUAUUAUGGCUGUGGAAGUUGUAGCUCCAAAUGAAUUUCAGGGACAAGUAAUUGCAGGAAUUAACCGACGCCAUGGGGUAAUCACUGGGCAAGAUGGAGUUGAGGACUAUUUUACACUGUAUGCAGAUGUCCCUCUAAAUGAUAUGUUUGGUUAUUCCACUGAACUUAGGUCAUGCACAGAGGGAAAGGGAGAAUACACAAUGGAGUAUAGCAGGUAUCAGCCAUGUUUACCAUCCACACAAGAAGACGUCAUUAAUAAGUAUUUGGAAGCUACAGGUCAACUUCCUGUUAAAAAAGGAAAAGCCAAGAACUAACUUUGCUUACUGUGAGUUGACUGACUCUAAUUGAAUCUGCGUGGUUUUGAUACUUUGAUGGAUUCCAGUGGAAUAAAUUCAGGCUGCUGAAACAAGAAAUUCUGAGCCCAGGAAGCGGGCUCUUCUUUCUUCAAAAGAAGCCCUUCUUGUUCAUAUUCAGGAGCUUCUGUUAUAUUCAAAGGUAAUUCUAUGUCUAUCUCAACUCUAUUGAUUGGUUUUAUAGUUCAUUGAAAAUCCUCAAAUAAAAUAUAAUUAUUACUGAAAUAUGUUUAAUAUUUAAGGGGAAAAGAGACUAAUUUCAGUUAUACUUUUAAGCUUAGAAUGUAUGUUCAUUUCCAAAUUUUGUAUCAUAAGAGUUUUCAACAUAGAGAAAAGCUGAAAAAAUGCAAAGAAUAACCACAUACUUUCCAUCUACCUUCCUUUGUUAACGGGUUGUUUAUCAUAUAAUAAUUUGUUUUGUCAUAUUUGCUUUCACUGUCUAUUAUCUGUUUAAGUCUCAUAACUCUAUUUUUAGUUUGCUGAAGACUUGAAAGUGAAUCGCAUAUAUCAUGACACUUCUUGGAGUGUCAUUAAUGGGCAGGCUUUUCUGUUGAAGAGUGGAUUCCGUAUGUUCUUCAUAGAGAGUGUUUUUCAGAUUCUUCAUUGGGAUAUUAAAAUAUUAGCCAAAUUUCUCUCUGUUUUAUAUAUGUCUGUUUAUUUCAGUUUGUGGUUUCUGCAAAUUUGUAACUGCCUCUGUUUUAGGAGUAUAAGUAUUACUUCCUUGUGGUCUAUUGUGAAGUAAAAAGUAGACCCUUGCAUAUACUAUUCUUGUUUGUGUUCAUCUUAAUGUUUUUGUACAGCUAAAUCAAAUGUAAUUUAUAGAGUUAGUUUCAUCAACCUAAUGAAUGCUAGUUAAAUUUGAAUUCCUUGGAAUUUAUCGUAUAUUGUAUUCACUGAGAUUAUGAAGGGACAAAUGUUAAUCUUUUGUUUCCAGAAAAAGUUGGGCUUUCCCAAGCAGUUCUAUUACCCGGUUCAGAAUUGCUUCAUCCAAAAAUCAUCUGAUGGUAUAGAUGGAUCCUAGUCCUUUUCAUUACCUGAUGGUAGAAAUAAAAUAAUUGAUUUUAAAUUCCUUUGCUUUUCUUGACUUAUAGACGUGGCUUUAUACUUUAAGGUUUCUAGGGGAAAAAGAUCUUUAAAAAGUAUUGAGCACAUGUUUUCAAGGCAUUUGCUAAAUACUUUUUUUUUUUUAAUUUUUAUUUUUUUGUGGUAGGGUCUCACUCUAUCCCCCAGGCUGGAAUGCAGAGGGACUAUCUCUGCUCACUACAACCUCUGCUUCCUGGGUUCAAGCAAUUAUCCCAUCUCAGCUGCCUAAGUAGGUGGGACUACAGGUGUGCGCCACCACUCCCUGCUAAUUUUUUGCAUUUUUUGAAGAGAUAGGGUUUUGCCAUAUUGCCCAGGCUGGUCUCAAACUCCUGGGCUCAAGCUCUCUGCCUGCCCCAGCCUCCCAAAGUGCUGGGAUUAUGGGCAUGAACCACCAUGCCUGGCUGCUAAAUACUUUAAAUGCAUUGUAUAAUUUCAUUCUCACAACCCCGAGAGUAAGUACUAUUAUUAUGUCCAUUUUGUAAUAGAAGAAGCACAGAUAAGGUAAAUAACUUUAAUGAGACCACAAAACCUAAGUUUUUUAAUUGAUACUUUAAUUACAAUUAUUCACCAAGUGCAUUUCCCCCAUGAAUGUCUGUUGCUACAGUAGCAUCAGGUCUGAAAAAAUGUGGUUGCUUUGGCAUUUCCUCAGCAUCUUGUGACAUUCACAAUAACUUUGAAUAUUGUUCCUAAUGAGGAAAUACAUUCUGUGUACCUUCAUGGAAUUUAGCAUGAUUCCUAUGGCUAUUGAGAAUAGUCACAACUACUGGAACUAAACUGGAUAAAUAAGUAAAAAACUUACUUAUUUUUAAUUUGUAAAACAUCCUGGUUAUAAUGUUACAGUGUUAGAAAAGGUCCUAGAUAUUUAAUCCAACACCAGCAUUUCAUAGGUAAUGAUUCAGGCCUAGCUGGUGGGAGUAAUUAGAAUAGGUUCACAAAUGGACAGAUCAGGACUAGAACCCACAUCUCUUUCUAAGUCAUUAGUUAUAGUUGGCAAAGAUCACAUACCAACCAAAGUCUGUAGCAUGGAAAAAAAUUAAUGAGAAUAUUCAUAGGUGAGGGUUGUUUAUACUACUAUCAAGAAGGAUAAUUGUUGGCUAAUUCAAAUAUUACAUCCUUGUAUUGGACAACAGUAGCAGCACUAGGUAGUAUUGUACUGAUUCCCAACCCUCACUGUACUUUAAAAAUCACUGGGGGAGCCUUAAAAAGAAAUACCUAGGCCUACACCCAGAUAUUUAGAUUAUUUGGCUGGAUCAAGAUAAAAACUUUUUUGGGUGAUUCUAAUAUGCAGACAAAGUUAAAGACCGCUGAAAUAUUGCCUGCACUGCGCUUAAGCCCAAGACAUGAAAUGAAAAAUCUGUGAAAUUCAGGAGUGUCAUAUUGUAUUCUUUUGUGUGAUAUUAGAGUUUGGUUUUUUUGUUUAACAACUGUUUUUUUUUUUAAGAGAUGGGGUCUUCUAAGACAAAAACCAUCUGACUCAGCAAUACCAUUACUAUAUACCCAAAGGAACGUAAAUCAUUCUAUUAUAAAGACACAUGCAUGCACACAUUCAUUGCAGAACUGUUCAUAAUGGCAAAGAUAUGGAAUCAACCUAAAUGCCUAUCACUGAUAGACUGGAUAAAGAAAAUGUGGUACAUACACAUUGUGGAAUACUAUGCAGCCAUAAAAAAAGAAUGAGAUCAAGUCCUUUGCAGGGACAUAGAUGGAGCUGGAAGCCAUUAUCCUCAUCAAACUAACAUAGGAAAAGAAAACCAAAUACUGCAUGUUCUCACUUAUAAGUGGGAGCUAAAUAAUGAGAACACAUGGACACACAGAGGGGAACAACACACACUGGGGCCUAUUGGAGGAUGGAGGGUGGGUGGAGGGAGAGGAUCAGGAAAAAUAACUAAUGGGUACUAGGCUUAAUACCUUGAUGAUGAAAUAAUCUGUACAACAAACCCCCAGGACACAAGUUUAGCUAUGUAACAAGCCUGCACAUCAACCCCUGAACUUAAAGAGAUGGGGUCUCGCUGUGUUUCCCAGGCUGCUCACAAAUUCAUGAGCUCAAGCAGUCCUCUGGCCUCAGCCUCUGGAGUAGCUGGGACAAGAGGCACACACCACCAUGCCUGGCUUGAUAACUUUACCUUAAAAAAAAAAGUGUUCCUAUUUAUAUAAGCUUCCAACUGACUUUCAAAAGAACUUGUUCAACUUCUAAAAAUUCGUAAUUCAGGUAGGAAGAAAAUGAAAGUAUGAAUAAAAUAAAAUGGAAUGUAGACAAAAUCCCUGGUAUUAUUUUAUAUGUCUUAAGAAAGUUCUAAAGGUAUUAGGAAAAUGAAUGUCAAGCUGUAUGUAAUUGUAAUUAGCUAAGAGUGAUUCAGAAUAAUUUAGACUGUUAAUGAAAAGAGGACAUAGGGAAUAGUUUUUCAUUUUAUGCCAAGUGAUUUUUCUGUUUUAUUAGCUAGUGAAACCAAUGUUGGUAAAAUUAAGUUAACAAUUUUAGAGUUUGUGCUAGAAAAGAUAUUCUGAGGCCGGAUGUGGUGGCUCACGCCUGUAAUUCCAGCACUUUGGGAGGCCAAGGUGGGUGGAUAACCUGAGGUCAGGAGUUCGAGACCACCCUGGCCAACACGGUGAAACCCCGUCUCUACUAUAAAUACAAAAAUCGUCCGGGCGGGGUGGCUCACGCCUGUAGCCCCAGCUGCUCAGGAGGCUGAGGCAGGAGGGUCGCUUGAACCCGGAAGGCGGAGGCUAUAGUGAGCUGAGAUGGCACCACUGCACUCCAGCACUCCAGCACUCCAGCCUAGGCAACAGAGUGAGACUCUGUCUCAAAAAAAAAAGAAAAAAAAGAAAAGAUGUUCUGAUGGUGAUACUGAUAAAUUUUUAGUUGGUUUAACUUUUUGGGUUUUGUAAAUUAAUAAAUUAGGUAAUUGUGUUUGUAUAUUAUUUGUAUGUAUAGAAUUCCCCCUCAUAAUCUAUUGUACUGUAAUAAAUCUGCUAAAAGGUUACCUUAGAAACAUUA